GGCUGUCUGAGGAGGGGCCACAGUGGAGACCAGUGCUGUGAGGGAGCCUCUGGUGGAGGUGGGUGCGGUGGUGCCUGCCCCCACCAGGCAGAUGGUGGCAAAUGCAAAGGCCCUGGGGUGGGAUGAGCCCAGGAUGGGACAGGCCAGUGUGGCCAUGGAGGUGGGGCAGCAGGGGCCAUGCACCAGGCAGAGAUUUUCUUCUGACUGCCUUGUGGAUGCCACUGAGGGGCUUUGAGCAGUGGCGGGGCAGAGUCUGCAUCUUUUGGCUGUGUGUGGGGAAUGGAGCUGGCAUCACUGGAAUCCAGGCCCUGCAUGAUUCCACUCCACAGAACUCGGAGGCAGAAGGGGAGAUGGGGCAGGACAGAGCCUAGUUCCAGAGCCAGGCAGGCCUGCUGCUGGUUUGGUUGGAAAUGCAUGGUGGGUGACUGGAGCUACUAUUUACUGAGGUGCAGGUGACCUGAGGCAUUCAGGGGCCCUGUAGAGCAGACAUCUUCAAACUCUCCCUCAGAGUGGGAGAAGACCCUGCCCCGGGGCCACGUCCGCUCCUCAAAAGGCUCCUCCUAAGGAAAGGUCCCUCCUCUUGCAGUCAUGGCCCUGGGGUGUGGAAACUGCGGGGUCCCAGCAGAUGUAAGGGUGUUGGGGAGUGGCUCCCCCGUGGGCCACAGGUCUGCAGCAGCUGCGGGAGCCUCUACACCAGCGGUGUUCAUGGUGAUCGUUGAUGACAAGUUGAUCUUUGAUGAAUUCAGGCUCAGAACUCAAGAGGAUGUGGCAUUGGGGGACUCUGCUGUGACCAAGCCCCUUCUGCUCCCGUCUCCUUAUUUCUGGAACCAGCUUCUCUGUGCUCGCAUUUCUAGAAAGAGGAAUAGGGACAGAGGCGAGCAUUUGUCCAUGCUAUGUGAACUGAUUAGGGGAAAAAAGCUCUUUCUCUUCUAUUAAACACAGCUUUUAUAUCAGAUGAUGAUUUAUCGAAGUGGAGACUAUUUCUGUUUUGAUCAGUGGUGUUCCAAUUGUAGUCACACUGUGAAAAGGAGAUAUGGUUCAAUGGUGGACCGCAUAUACCAUGCUGGUCCUGUAAGAUGAUAGGACCGCAUUUUUUACGUUACCUUUUCUAUGUUUAGAUAAGCAAAUACUUACUAUUGUGUUACAGGUACCUACAGUAUUCCGUUAGUUAAGUGCUGUACAGGUUUGCAGCCUAGGAGUCGUAGGCUGGGCCGUAUAGCCUAGGUGUGUAGUAGGCUAUACCAUCUAGGGUUGUGUAUGUACACUCUAUCAUGUUUGCACAACUACAAAAUCCCAUAGCAAUGCAUUUCUCAGAAUCCUGUCAGGAAGCUACACACGAGUGUACUGCGGUGAUGAUUCGGGAGACGUUAGCACAGCCCUAUGGUUGUAGGAAAUCAAGACGAAUUCAAUUUAUAUGCAUGUUUGUGUUGCAAAAAGUUACAGUAGGGUGAAUCAAUAGAGUGAUUUCAAGCAUGAAUAUAUAACGUUGGGUUUACAUUUUGUAGUAACAGAAAUAGGAGUUCCUAGAGGAAGAAGUGUAUACUUUCUGGCCUUAAGAAGAGCUUGUUCGUGUGCGUUGUAAAUAGAUGGCCAUGGCUGUCACGUCACCGUGCCUAGAUUCUAAUAGAUAUAUUUACAAGAGUGACAUGGCAGUUUUAUUUUAACUCAGUAUUUACAGUAUGCUGGAAAUGAUGUCCCUUGCAGCUGUUUAAAACAGGGAUGAACAGUUUAUACUGUCAGCUGAGAUGCAGGGAGUGGCAUUUUAGGAAAUAUUUUCAUGGGGAUACUGGCAAAACUCAAAGAGCCUGGCUGCUCCUGGUUCCAGGCAUCAGGUGGAGCUGCCGUCCGGGGCCUGGCAGGGCGAGGGGCCGCCAGGAUGCCGGCUUGGGAGUUGGGGGUGGCAGGUAAGUGCUGCAUGUAGAGGGACGGAGGUCUAGGUAGCCAGCUUGGGGUACCCCCUGUGGAGGCUCUGGAGGGGAGGUGCAGACAGCAAAGGGGCUUAGGAGGGAGCACGCAGUGAGAGGGACCCUCCAGGGCAGAAGGGAUUUCCAGAGGAGGCAGUAAGGAUGGCUUCGGGUGGAGAGGACCUGGGAUUGGGCAGGGACCCUGCUGAAGCCACUCGUCCUACAUGAAUCCUACUCAGAGCAGGAGAAGCCAAGAUCAGCGAUCCUCCCGUCUUGGCCCCCCAAAGUGCUGGGAUGACAGGUGUCAGCCUGUCCUGGAGUCCUCCAAGCCCGUGGGGUCUGAUGAGCACAGACGGCUCAGCUCUUCCUUGCUUCCAUACCCUUACAUAAAACUGGAGCUCGGCUUUCUCAGAGAGGAUGCUUUUAUUUGCCUGAGAUGCACCAUCUGUUACUGGCUCCGUUUGACCGAUCUCCUUGUUCAUCGUGGUCCAGGUCUGCACCUGACAGCUCUGAGUGCUGACCUACUGCAGGCGUCAUCAGUAAACCUUGACUAAGUGAUGCGGCUCACGGCAAACUCACUGUGUCAGAGAUGGCUGAAGAUGGGAGCGAAGAGAUCAUGUUCAUCUGGUGUGAAGACUGCAGCCAGUACCACGACUCCGAAUGUCCCGAGCUGGGCCCAGUGGUCAUGGUCAAAGACUCCUUUGUGUUAAGCAGGGCAAGGUCAUCCCUUCCUCCCAACUUGGAGAUCAGACGACUGGAAGAUGGAGCCGAGGGGGUGUUCGCCAUCACUCAGCUCGUCAAGCGGACACAGUUCGGUCCCUUUGAGUCCAGGAGGGUCGCCAAAUGGGAAAAGGAGUCUGCAUUUCCCCUGAAGGUGUUCCAGAAGGACGGGCACCCCGUGUGCUUCGACACCUCCAACGAGGAUGACUGCAACUGGAUGAUGCUGGUGCGGCCAGCGGCGGAGGCCGAGCACCAGAACCUGACGGCCUACCAGCACGGCAGCGACGUGUACUUCACCACCUCCAGAGACAUCCCCCCGGGUACCGAGCUGCGCGUGUGGUAUGCGGCCUUCUAUGCCAAGAAGAUGGACAAGCCCAUGCUGAAGCAGGCCGGCUCUGGCGUCCACGCUGCAGGCACCCCAGAAAACAGCGCCCCCGUGGAGUCGGAGCCCAGCCAGUGGGCGUGUAAAGUGUGUUCUGCCACCUUCCUGGAGCUGCAGCUCCUCAAUGAACAUCUGUUGGGCCACUUAGAACAAGCCAAAAGCCUUCCUCCAGGCAGCCAAAGCGAGGCAGCAGCUCCCGAGAAGGAGCAGGACACACCCCGGGGGGAACCCCCUGCAGUGCCCGAGAGCGAGAAUGUUGCCACCAAAGAACAGAAGAAAAAGCCUCGAAGGGGGAGAAAACCCAAAGUGUCCAAAGCUGAGCAGCCUCUAGUCAUCGUGGAAGACAAGGAACCCACAGAGCAAGUGGCAGAGAUCAUUACCGAGGUCCCUCCGGAUGAGCCUGUGAGUGCAACGCCAGAUGAGCGGAUCAUGGAGCUGGUUCUGGGGAAGCUGGCCACCACCACCACUGACACCAGCUCGGUUCCAAAGUUCACCCAUCAUCAGAAUAACACCAUCACGCUCAAGAGGAGCUUAAUUCUCUCAAGCAGACACGGCAUCCGGCGCAAGCUCAUCAAACAGCUCGGGGAGCACAAGCGGGUUUACCAGUGCAAUAUCUGCAGCAAGAUCUUCCAGAACAGCAGCAACCUGAGCAGGCACGUGCGCUCGCAUGGUGACAAGCUGUUUAAGUGCGAAGAGUGUGCAAAAUUGUUCAGCCGCAAAGAGAGCCUAAAGCAGCACGUUUCCUACAAGCACAGCAGGAACGAGGUGGACGGCGAGUACAGGUACCGCUGCGGCACUUGUGAGAAGACCUUCCGCAUCGAGAGCGCGCUGGAGUUCCACAACUGCAGGACAGGACUCAUAGCACACCCUGGAGAGGGGGGGCCCGGCGGCAGUCGGCUUAGAGACCUACCAGAUGACAAGACGUUCCAAUGUGAGAUGUGUUUCAGAUUCUUCUCCACCAACAGCAACCUCUCCAAGCACAAGAAGAAGCACGGCGACAAGAAGUUUGCCUGUGAGGUCUGCAGCAAGAUGUUCUACCGCAAGGACGUCAUGCUGGACCACCAGCGCCGGCACCUGGAAGGAGUGCGGCGAGUGAAGCGAGAGGACCUGGAGGCCGGUGGGGAGAACCUGGUCCGUUACAAGAAGGAGCCUUCCGGGUGCCCGGUGUGUGGCAAGGUGUUCUCCUGCCGGAGCAAUAUGAACAAGCACCUGCUCACCCACGGCGACAAGAAGUACACCUGCGAGAUCUGCGGGCGCAAGUUCUUCCGCGUGGAUGUGCUCAGGGACCACAUCCAUGUCCACUUCAAGGACAUCGCGUUGAUGGAUGACCACCAGAGGGAAGAGUUUAUCGGCAAGAUCGGGAUCUCCUCGGAAGAAAACGAUGACAAUUCUGACGAGAGCGCAGACUCGGAGCCUCACAAGUACAGCUGCAAGCGGUGCCAGCUCACCUUCGGCCGGGGGAAGGAGUACCUGAAGCACAUCAUGGAGGUGCACAAGGAGAAGGGCUAUGGCUGCAGCAUCUGCAACCGGCGCUUUGCACUGAAGGCCACCUACCACGCCCACAUGGUCAUCCACCGUGAAAACCUGCCGGACCCCAACGUGCAGAAGUACAUCCACCCCUGCGAGAUCUGCGGGCGGAUCUUCAACAGCAUCGGGAACCUGGAGCGCCACAAGCUCAUCCACACAGGUGUGAAGAGCCACGCCUGCGAGCAGUGUGGGAAGUCCUUUGCCAGGAAGGACAUGCUGAAGGAGCACAUGCGUGUGCACGACAAUGUCCGCGAGUACCUGUGUGCCGAGUGUGGGAAAGGCAUGAAGACCAAGCACGCGCUGCGCCACCACAUGAAGCUGCACAAGGGCAUCAAGGAGUACGAGUGCAAGGAGUGCCACCGCAGGUUCGCGCAGAAGGUCAACAUGCUCAAGCACUGCAAGCGGCACACGGGGAUUAAAGAUUUCAUGUGUGAAUUGUGUGGGAAGACAUUCAGCGAGAGGAACACCAUGGAGACCCACAAGCUCAUCCACACAGUGGGCAAGCAGUGGACGUGCUCCGUGUGCGACAAGAAGUACGUGACCGAGUACAUGCUGCAGAAGCACGUUCAGCUCACACACGACAAGGUGGAGGCGCAGAGCUGCCAGCUGUGCGGGACCAAGGUGUCCACCAGGGCCUCCAUGAGCCGACACAUGCGGCGCAAGCACCCCGAGGUGCUCGCGGUGAGGAUCGAUGACCUGGACCACCUCCCGGAGACCACCACCAUCGACGCCUCCUCCAUUGGCAUCGUCCAGCCUGAGCUGACUCUGGAGCAGGAGGAUUUGGCCGAAGGGAAGCACGGGAAAGCUGCCAAGCGAAGUCACAAGAGAAAGCAGAAGCCAGAAGAGGAGGCGGGUGCUCCGGUGCCCGAGGACGCCACCUUCAGCGAAUACUCAGAGAAAGAGACGGAGUUCACAGGCAGUGUAGGCGACGAGACCAAUUCCGCAGUACAGAGCAUUCAGCAGGUAGUGGUGACCCUGGGUGACCCAAAUGUGACCACACCAUCGAGCUCAGUCGGCUUAACCAACAUCACCGUGACCCCCAUCACCACUGCGGCCGCGACUCAGUUUACCAAUCUCCAGCCGGUGGCCGUGGGGCACCUUACCACCCCUGAACGCCAGUUACAGCUGGACAACUCAAUCCUGACCGUGACCUUUGAUACCGUCAGCGGCUCUGCCAUGUUGCACAACCGCCAAAAUGACGUCCAGAUCCACCCCCAGCCGGAAGCCUCGAACCCACAGUCUGUGGCCCAUUUCAUCAACCUGACGACCCUGGUCAACUCCAUCACGCCCCUGGGGAGCCAGCUUAGUGACCAGCACCCGCUCACGUGGCGGGCAGUGCCCCAGACUGACGUCUUGCCACCCUCGCAGCCGCAGGCACCCCCACAGCAGGCGGCCCAGCCCCAGGUGCAGGCGGAGCAGCAGCAGCAGCAGAUGUACAGCUACUGAGCUGCGUUCCGGGAGACUCGGGGCAAGAACUGCAGAGGGAUGUUUGGGAUUUGUUUAGAUGUGUUUGCUGGAUACCAAACAAACAAAAAGUCAUACAUUGCAAUGUAAGGUUGACUUAGCUUUGCAGAGUAUCUCCAGAUCCCCCGCCAGCAACCAUUACGGUCUGUCAGCUUAACUCUAGAAGGGACCUCUGGCAGGCCAGAGUUUUAAACUGGAUGGGGCUCCACACCAUGCCUUACCAAGGCAGUAAGUCCUGGGCCGGGGCCGCAUCUGCCUCCCCUUACAGAACCAGUGUUCGCCCGACACAGGGUUCGGGAAAGUGAAGCUGAGAGAGAAGCAGGAUUUUAAGAGGCAGGAGAUAAGUUAUUAGGAACACAAAUGGUUCAUUUUCUUUUUUCUUUUAGAGCUCGGUUCCUAUGAGAACACAGACAGUAUUCACAGGUGGCAGCAGGCAGCAGGGAACAUUUUCUCCUCACUUCUGGAUUUUUUUGCAAGCGAGCACAUAGAAGUUAAAGUAACGUGUAUUCUCUUUGAACUAGGAGUGGAGUCGGUUCUUAUACAACUAUGGGCUGAAACCAUGAGGCGUGCUGAGCCGCACCUGAUCCUGCAACCUUCGAGGUCAUCACGGUCAUCAUGUGCAAGGGGUCACGUGAGGUCACUGACUCCAGCUCAAAACGCAUCUUAGUAAUAUCCAUGAAUCGAUUUCCAAUAGAGUUUUUUUCCUUUUUUUUUUUUAACUUUAUUUCAAACAUACAUUAUGUGUUCAAGACUGUUAUGGCCAAUAUUGUGUUUUAGUUUUAUGUUAACAUGAUAAAGUCAUGUGCACUGUAGGACCAUCUGUCCCUGUCCACCCUUCACAGCUGCCCAGAUGCAGAGGGUCGCGCGGCUGUGUGUGAGGAGUGAGCCUCCCUGCUGCCCCCAGGGGCUCCUCCGGGUUGUCUCAGGAUUCUCUGCAAUCCAAAUGUAUCCAUUCUGGCUGAAGCCCAGCCAGAAUCCCGAGUGGAAGAAACGGGGGAAAAGUCAUAUUUUCCUUCUGUUUAAACUUCAAUUCCAAAGGUUGGUGUAUUUCAUGACCAGUUUUCUAUAAAAAUAUUGAAUGAGUUUGGCUCUUUACAAUGGAAAAGUGUAGGUAUUUCUGAAACACAGAGAAAAUGCUAUUUCCUGCCAGGUGGUAAUGAAAGCAGAGAGGUUAGUUCACUAAUAGAAGCAUUAAUUGCCCCUAAAACUGAAUGUGCGGUGAACAGCCAGGUCUGCGUGUGCGGGGACACGUGCUGUCACGUCUGUGUACCAGUUUCGGGGGCAGGGGCCAGGGUUGGGGGAGGCACCCAGCCCUCCUGCUGCCCACGACAAGAAACACUGAGAGGUGUGGGGAGAAGUUUGCUCUUAACUUUCCUGGUACUCUGUUUGUGGCCACAGUGAGAGGACAAACCUGCCUUAAGGUGUCCUGCUUUGCCAGUUAUCCCAGAUCCUGCACUCACUGGGAGUCCAUCUUGAGGAAACACUGGCAUGGCUGAGUAAUUGAUCAGGAGCAGUCCUGAUGUUGCCAGCAGAACAAAGGAUGAUUGUGUUUUUCAAAACGCAACUUUCUCAGCACUUCACUCCAAACAGCAGACUUUUGAGGACAGGGCUGGAAUUUGUUUUGUGCAAUAUAUGCCUUCAUGAACUAAGGAAUGUUCAUCCCCAGGCAGCAUGCAGGAGGGUCUGUGGGGCUCACCUCCUCACCUUACCCACCAUCACUCGCGCCUAGCUCUCACCUCUCAGUUGAAUGAAUAGUGGGAGAUCAUUUGACUUUUAAUUUAUGAGAAUUAUUUUAUGUUAUUUAUGUAUAUAAUUAACUGUUUUAUACAUAGUAGUCUCAUCAAAUGAAUUCGGGCUUGGGGUGAUAUUGUCUCCAUUCUCCAGAUACAAGUGCUCCAGGCAUCCAUGGAAUCAGCAGGAGACCAGGGCUCCUAAGAUAUAUUUUUAAAAAUCAGUAUCGAUUUCUUUUUGCCUUUGCAGAAUCUAAAGGGCAAAUGACCUCGCAGAGACUCCCAACGGGCUUUGGGCUCAUGACGAAACACCCACUAGCAUUGAUCUUUUAUUCCUCUUCCCUAUAAAAUAAAGGCCUUGGAAAUCACAAUUUUAUUUUUUUAAAGAAGUUGUUUUAGUGCCUAGAGUAAGACCGCAUCAAAUGUUGUUAAAGAACCUAAUUUAGAUUGUGUGGUAUAUACCACUGUUUAUCUCAAUACACAGACACCUCUUACUUCUUGUUAUAAGUGAGAACUCUAAAGAAAAAUCAAACUCCCAAGUUUUCUGUAAACAUACGUGGUCUUAAUAGGGUCACUGUCUGAGGCAAAAUGGGUUGUCUUAAAGCAAUUGCUACAAAUUUGCAUCAAAGAAACUAGAUAGCAAAAUACAACAACCAUGUACCACCCAGGCAGAAGAGUCCUCACCUAUACGCAGUUCUGCAUAUUGAUCAUCAUGACAGGAAGUAUUUCGUUUUUUAACUGAUCCCAGGUGCACAGAUGUAUUCAUAAAGGAAGACAUUAGAUCCAGCCAUUGUGGCCACCAGGCUCUGUGGACCCAUCUCAGUGGAGAAUUCGUUUUGGACCCGUGGCUCCGUGCAGCUGUGGACUCGAGUGCCAUCCACUGGUGUGAGUCUUGCGGGGAGGCCACAGGUACAGCUGCUCCCCGUGAAUCCUGGUCUGUGGGUUGAGAAGGGGCUCGGGCCUCUGGAAUGCUCUAGCGUGUGACGUGUUCUCAGGAAAACGUUCUGUGCCAAGUGCCGCCUCGCUGUGUCCGGCAUGGGACUGCGCUGGAGGGUCCGGCGUGGAAGGCAGACCUCCUGUACCUCUAUCGUUCCCAUUUGUGGCAUCCAAAGGCGGAAGGCUCAUGGCUUCCCCACUAGAGGCGGCGUCUUGGGCUUUCCCAUUGGAUUGUGAAAGGCAUUAAGACUGUUUGGAGAUGUUGGCUGUAUUUCCUGUCACAUCAGGUUGUAUGAUGACGAAUAAAAGGUGCUGUGACCCGUGUUUUCAA